GAAGCCUGCCCAACGAUCGUGGGCAGGAGGUGGUUUCUGGUUUGUUGGGGCGUGUGUAUGUGUAUUUGGGGGGACUGAAGGGUACGUGGGGCGAAACAAAACCGGCCAUGGCAGCAGCGGAGGAGGAGGACGGGGGCCCCGAAGGGCCAAAUCGCGAGCGGGGCGGGGCGGGCGCGACCUUCGAAUGUAAUAUAUGUUUGGAGACUGCUCGGGAAGCUGUGGUCAGUGUGUGUGGCCACCUGUACUGUUGGCCAUGUCUUCAUCAGUGGCUGGAGACACGGCCAGAACGGCAAGAGUGUCCAGUAUGUAAAGCUGGGAUCAGCAGAGAGAAGGUUGUCCCGCUUUAUGGGCGAGGGAGCCAGAAGCCCCAGGAUCCCAGAUUAAAAACUCCACCCCGCCCCCAGGGCCAGAGACCAGCUCCGGAGAGCAGAGGGGGAUUCCAGCCAUUUGGUGAUACCGGGGGCUUCCACUUCUCAUUUGGUGUUGGUGCUUUUCCCUUUGGCUUUUUCACCACCGUCUUCAAUGCCCAUGAGCCUUUCCGCCGGGGUACAGGUGUGGAUCUGGGACAGGGUCACCCAGCCUCCAGCUGGCAGGAUUCCCUCUUCCUGUUUCUCGCCAUCUUCUUCUUUUUUUGGCUGCUCAGUAUUUGAGCUAUGUCUGCUUCCUGCCCACCUCCAGCCAGAGAAGAAUCAGUAUUGAGGGUCCCUGCUGACCCUUCCGUACUCCUGGACCCCCUUGACCCCUCUAUUUCUGUUGGCUAAGGCCAGCCCUGGACAUUGUCCAGGAAGGCCUGGGGAGGAGGAGUGAAGUCUGUGCAUAGAUGGGAGAGCCUUCUGCUCAGAGGCUCACUCAGUAACGUUGUUUAAUUCUCUGCCCUGGGGAAGGAGGAUGGAUUGAGAGAAUGUCUUUCUCCUCUCCUAAGUCUUUGCUUUCCCUGAUUUCUUGAUUUGAUCUUCAAAGGUGGGCAAAGUUCCCUCUGACUCUUCCCCCACUCCCCAUCUUACUGAUUUAAUUUAAUUUUUCACUCCCCAGAGUCUAAUAUGGAUUCUGACUCUUAAGUGCUUCCGCCCCCUCACUACCUCCUUUAAUACAAAUUCAAUAAAAAAGGUGAAAUAUA